GCAGUCGCCGCAGCGUCCGGACCGGAACCAGCGCCGUCCGCGGAGCCGCCGCCGCCGCCGCCGGGCCCUUUCCAAGCCGGGCGCUCGGAGCUGUGCCCGGCCCCGCUUCAGCACCGCGGACAGCGCCGGCCGCGUGGGGCUGAGCCCCGAGCCCCCGCGCACGCUUCAGCGCCCCUUCCCUCGGCCGACGUCCCGGGACCGCCGCUCCGGGGGAGACGUGGCGUCCGCAGCCCGCGGGGCCGGGCGAGCGCAGGACGGCCCGGAAGCCCCGCGGGGGAUGCGCCGAGGGCCCCGCGUUCGCGCCGCGCAGAGCCAGGCCCGCGGCCCGAGCCCAUGAGCACCAUGCGCCUGCUGACGCUCGCCCUGCUGUUCUCCUGCUCCGUCGCCCGUGCCGCGUGCGACCCCAAGAUCGUCAACAUUGGCGCGGUGCUGAGCACGCGGAAGCACGAGCAGAUGUUCCGCGAGGCCGUGAACCAGGCCAACAAGCGGCACGGCUCCUGGAAGAUUCAGCUCAAUGCCACCUCCGUCACGCACAAGCCCAACGCCAUCCAGAUGGCUCUGUCGGUGUGCGAGGACCUCAUCUCCAGCCAGGUCUACGCCAUCCUAGUUAGCCAUCCACCUACCCCCAACGACCACUUCACUCCCACCCCUGUCUCCUACACAGCCGGCUUCUACCGCAUACCCGUGCUGGGGCUGACCACCCGCAUGUCCAUCUACUCGGACAAGAGCAUCCACCUGAGCUUCCUGCGCACCGUGCCGCCCUACUCCCACCAGUCCAGCGUGUGGUUUGAGAUGAUGCGUGUCUACAGCUGGAACCACAUCAUCCUGCUGGUCAGCGACGACCACGAGGGCCGGGCGGCUCAGAAACGCCUGGAGACGCUGCUGGAGGAGCGUGAGUCCAAGAGUAAAAAAAGGAACUAUGAAAACCUCGACCAACUGUCCUAUGACAACAAGCGCGGACCCAAGGCAGAGAAGGUGCUGCAGUUUGACCCAGGGACCAAGAACGUGACGGCCCUGCUGAUGGAGGCGAAAGAGCUGGAGGCCCGGGUCAUCAUCCUUUCUGCCAGCGAGGACGAUGCUGCCACUGUAUACCGCGCAGCCGCGAUGCUGAACAUGACGGGCUCCGGGUACGUGUGGCUGGUCGGCGAGCGCGAGAUCUCGGGGAACGCCCUGCGCUACGCCCCAGACGGCAUCCUCGGGCUGCAGCUCAUCAACGGCAAGAACGAGUCGGCCCACAUCAGCGACGCCGUGGGCGUGGUGGCCCAGGCCGUGCACGAGCUCCUCGAGAAGGAGAACAUCACCGACCCGCCGCGGGGCUGCGUGGGCAACACCAACAUCUGGAAGACCGGGCCGCUCUUCAAGAGAGUGCUGAUGUCUUCCAAGUAUGCGGAUGGGGUGACUGGUCGCGUGGAGUUCAAUGAGGAUGGGGACCGGAAGUUCGCCAACUACAGCAUCAUGAACCUGCAGAACCGCAAGCUGGUGCAAGUGGGCAUCUACAAUGGCACCCACGUCAUCCCUAAUGACAGGAAGAUCAUCUGGCCAGGCGGAGAGACAGAGAAGCCUCGAGGGUACCAGAUGUCCACCAGACUGAAGAUUGUGACGAUCCACCAGGAGCCCUUCGUGUACGUCAAGCCCACGCUGAGUGAUGGGACAUGCAAGGAGGAGUUCACAGUCAACGGCGACCCAGUCAAGAAGGUGAUCUGCACCGGGCCCAACGACACGUCGCCGGGCAGCCCCCGCCACACGGUGCCUCAGUGUUGCUACGGCUUUUGCAUCGACCUGCUCAUCAAGCUGGCACGGACCAUGAACUUCACCUACGAGGUGCACCUGGUGGCAGAUGGCAAGUUCGGCACACAGGAGCGGGUGAACAACAGCAACAAGAAGGAGUGGAAUGGGAUGAUGGGCGAGCUGCUCAGCGGGCAGGCAGACAUGAUCGUGGCGCCGCUAACCAUAAACAACGAGCGCGCGCAGUACAUCGAGUUUUCCAAGCCCUUCAAGUACCAGGGCCUGACUAUUCUGGUCAAGAAGGAGAUUCCCCGGAGCACGCUGGACUCGUUCAUGCAGCCGUUCCAGAGCACACUGUGGCUGCUGGUGGGGCUGUCGGUGCACGUGGUGGCCGUGAUGCUGUACCUGCUGGACCGCUUCAGCCCCUUCGGCCGGUUCAAGGUGAACAGCGAGGAGGAGGAGGAGGACGCACUGACCCUGUCCUCGGCCAUGUGGUUCUCCUGGGGCGUCCUGCUCAACUCCGGCAUCGGGGAAGGCGCCCCCAGAAGCUUCUCAGCGCGCAUCCUGGGCAUGGUGUGGGCCGGCUUUGCCAUGAUCAUCGUGGCCUCCUACACCGCCAACCUGGCGGCCUUCCUGGUGCUGGACCGGCCGGAGGAGCGCAUCACGGGCAUCAACGACCCUCGGCUGAGGAACCCCUCGGACAAGUUUAUCUACGCCACGGUGAAGCAGAGCUCCGUGGAUAUCUACUUCCGGCGCCAGGUGGAGCUGAGCACCAUGUACCGGCAUAUGGAGAAGCACAACUACGAGAGUGCGGCGGAGGCCAUCCAGGCCGUGAGAGACAACAAGCUGCAUGCCUUCAUCUGGGACUCGGCGGUGCUGGAGUUCGAGGCCUCGCAGAAGUGCGACCUGGUGACGACUGGAGAGCUGUUUUUCCGCUCGGGCUUCGGCAUAGGCAUGCGCAAAGACAGCCCCUGGAAGCAGAACGUCUCCCUGUCCAUCCUCAAGUCCCACGAGAAUGGCUUCAUGGAAGACCUGGACAAGACGUGGGUUCGGUAUCAGGAAUGUGACUCGCGCAGCAACGCCCCUGCGACCCUUACUUUUGAGAACAUGGCCGGGGUCUUCAUGCUGGUAGCUGGGGGCAUCGUGGCCGGGAUCUUCCUGAUUUUCAUCGAGAUUGCCUACAAGCGGCACAAGGAUGCUCGCCGGAAGCAGAUGCAGCUGGCCUUUGCCGCCGUUAACGUGUGGCGGAAGAACCUGCAGGAUAGAAAGAGUGGUAGAGCAGAGCCUGACCCUAAAAAGAAAGCCACAUUUAGGGCUAUCACCUCCACCCUGGCUUCCAGCUUCAAGAGGCGUAGGUCCUCCAAAGACACGAGCACCGGGGGUGGACGCGGCGCUUUGCAAAACCAAAAAGACACAGUGCUGCCGCGACGCGCUAUUGAGAGGGAGGAGGGCCAGCUGCAGCUGUGUUCCCGUCAUAGGGAGAGCUGAGACUCCCCGCCCGCCCUCCUCUGCCCCCUCCCCCGCAGACAGACAGACAGACGGACGGGACAGCGGCCCGGCCCACGCAGAGCCCCGGAGCACCACGGGGUCGGGGGAGGAGCACCCCCAGCCUCCCCCAGGCUGCGCCUGCCCGCCCGCCGGUUGGCCGGCUGGCCGGUCCACCCCGUCCCGGCCCCGCGCGUGCCCCCAGCGUGGGGCUAACGGGCGCCUUGUCUGUGUAUUUCUAUUUUGCAGCAGUACCAUCCCACUGAUAUCACGGGCCCGCUCAACCUCUCAGAUCCCUCGGUCAGCACCGUGGUGUGAGGCCCCCGGAGGCGCCCACCUGCCCAGUUAGCCCGGCCAAGGACACUGAUGGGUCCUGCUGCUCGGGAAGGCCUGAGGGAAGCCCACCCGCCCCAGAGACUGCCCACCCUGGGCCUCCCGUCCGUCCGCCCGCCCACCCCGCUGCCUGGCGGGCAGCCCCUGCUGGACCAAGGUGCGGACCGGAGCGGCUGAGGACGGGGCAGAGCUGAGUCGGCUGGGCAGGGCCGCAGGGCGCUCCGGCAGAGGCAGGGCCCUGGGGUCUCUGAGCAGUGGGGAGCGGGGGCUAACUGGCCCCAGGCGGAGGGGCUUGGAGCAGAGACGGCAGCCCCAUCCUUCCCGCAGCACCAGCCUGAGCCACAGUGGGGCCCAUGGCCCCAGCUGGCUGGGUCGCCCCUCCUCGGGCGCCUGCGCUCCUCUGCAGCCUGAGCUCCACCCUCCCCUCUUCUUGCGGCACCGCCCACCCACACCCCGUCUGCCCCUUGACCCCACACGCCGGGGCUGGCCCUGCCCUCCCCCACGGCCGUCCCUGACUUCCCAGCUGGCAGCGCCUCCCGCCGCCUCGGGCCGCCUCCUCCAGACUCGAGAGGGCUGAGCCCCUCCUCUCCUCGUCCGGCCUGCAGCCCAGAACGGGCCUCCCCGGGGGUCCCCGGACGCUGGCUCGGGACUGUCUUCAACCCUGCCCUGCACCUUGGGCACGGGAGAGCGCCACCCGCCCGCCCCCGCCCUCGCUCCGGGUGCGUGACCGGCCCGCCACCUUGUACAGAACCAGCACUCCCAGGGCCCGAGCGCGUGCCUUCCCCGUGCGGCCCGUGCGCAGCCGCGCUCUGCCCCUCCGUCCCCAGGGUGCAGGCGCGCACCGCCCAACCCCCACCUCCCGGUGUAUGCAGUGGUGAUGCCUAAAGGAAUGUCACGCA